CUUUUUUUCUGAGCAGUAGGUCUCAUUAGUGAGCUUAGAAUACUCCAUAAACCAUGCUGUAAACAGAUGCACUGUCAUCCAGGCUUUGUUAUUCCAUUUCCAACACAGGCAGAGUGGAUUUAGCAUCAUUCUUAAGGGUCCUAGAAUUUUUGGAAUGGGAAAUGACCAUUGGCUUCACGUCACCAGCUGCAUUCGCCCCUAACGAGAGUCAGCCUGUCCUUUUCAAUCUUUGAAGCCAGGCAUUGACUUCUCUCUAGCUGCGAAAGUCCUAGAUGCCAUCUUCUUCCAAUAGAAAGCGGUUUUAUCCACACUGAAAAUCUUUUUAGAGUAGCCACCUUAGUCAACCAUCUUAGCUAGAUCUGGAGAACUUGCUUCAGUUUCUCCUGUAAAGCUUGCAGCUUCACCUUGCACUUCUAUGUGUGGAAGUGACUUCUUUCCUUAAACCUCAUGAACCAACCUCUGCUGGUUUUCUGCUUUUCUUCCGCAGCUUCCGUCACCCAUCUCGGCCUUCAUAGAAUUGAGGACGGUUAGGACCUUGCUGUGGAUUCAGCUUUGGUUGCCAGUCACACCAGCCGUCGGGCAAAGUUGUUGUUUUAAUCUCUCCAGACCACUCAGACUUCUUCCACAUCAGCAAUAAGGCUGUCUUGCUAUCCUGUCAUUUGUGUGUUCACUGGAGCAGCUCGUUUAAUUUCCUUCUGGGGCUUUUCCUUUGCAUUGCCGCUCAGCCGUUUGAUGCAAGAGGCCCGGCUUUCUGACUGAGUUUUAGACAUGCGUUCCUCACAAAGCUUAAUCAUUUCUAGCUUUUGGUUUAAAGUGAGAGAUGUGGGAUUCCUCCUUUCACGUGAGAGGCCAUGGUAAGGUUACUAAUUAGCCUAAUCUCAAUAUUGUUAUAUCCAGGGAAGGGGGAGGCUGGAGGAAAGGGAGAGAUGGGGAACAGCCGGUUGGUGGUGGAUGUAGGAAACACACAUUGAUAAUUCAGCUUCUUAUAUGGGUGCGGUUCAUGGUGCCCCAAACAGUGACAGUAGUUUUAGAUUCCUGUUACCUGCCGGGCACCUGGCAUGGGUGUGGAGGGCAGAGUUCUGAGGUGGUCUCUUAGAUUCCUGGCCCCUAAUGUACACACCCCUUCUUCCAGUUACUCAUUCAGACACUCAUCUGGUACUGUCAUGAAGAGACUUGCAGAUGUCGGGAGGUCCCAGGUCAGUGAGGUGAGAAGGGAGGUCGUCUGGGAGAGCCUGACCUAAUCACACAGACCCUGGGAAGCAGAGGUUCCUCCAUCUGGUUGGAGAACAGAGGCUGAGAUUAGAUGCGUGAGAAAAAUGUGAUGUGCUGUGCCUGCCUUGAGAUUCAGGUGGCCCCUAGGGACGGCUCCUGCUCACAGCCAGUAAGCACACAGGGUUCUUAGUCCUACAGUUGCAGGGAACUGGAUUCUGCCACGAAAUCUGAAUGAGUUUGGAAACCAGUUUUCCCCAGGGCCUCCAGGUGAGAGCUCAGCCCGAUGACAUACAGUUGCAGCUUUGCGUGACCCUGCGUGGAGAUCCCAGCUGGCCUGGCCUGGAUGUGUGACCUGCAGAACUGUAGGAUUCUAAUGUAGGAACUGGUGAGAAGAAGGUGACUGAAGCCUGGAUUUCUGAGGAUGAAAACUCACAUAGGACGACGUCAGACAGACUCACGGUGAUGGAGCUCCCCUCUCCCGAGUCUGAGGAAGUCCACGAGCCCAGAUUAGGGGAGCUCUUGGGAAAUCCAGAAGGUCAGAGCCUGGGGAGUUCCCCCUCUCAGGACAGGGGCUGCAAGCAGGUGACAGUGACCCAUUGGAAGAUCCAGACAGGAGAGACAGCUCAAGUGUGCACCAAGUCAGGAAGAAACCAUAUUCUGAACUCAGACCUUCUUCUGCUUCAGAGAGAGCUCAUAGAGGGGGAAGCCAAUCCUUGCGAUAUCUGUGGCAAAACCUUCACGUUUAAUUCGGACCUAGUUAGGCAUCGGAUUUCGCAUGCUGGGGAGAAACCUUACACGUGCGAUCAGUGUGGGAAAGGCUUUGGCCAGAGCUCACACCUUAUGGAGCAUCAGAGAAUUCACACUGGAGAGAGACUCUACGUCUGUAAUGUGUGUGGGAAAGACUUCAUUCACUAUUCAGGUCUCAUUGAGCAUCAGCGCGUUCAUUCAGGAGAAAAGCCCUUCAAAUGUGCGCAGUGUGGGAAGGCGUUUUGUCACAGUUCAGACCUGAUUAGGCACCAGAGAGUUCACACCAGAGAGAGACCUUUUGAAUGCAAAGAGUGUGGGAAAGGCUUCAGUCAGAGCUCCUUACUUAUUCGCCAUCAGAGGAUUCACACGGGAGAAAGGCCCUAUGAGUGCAAUGAAUGUGGGAAAUCCUUCAUAAGGAGCUCGAGCCUCAUUCGCCAUUAUCAGAUCCACACAGAAGUGAAACAGUAUGAAUGCAAAGAAUGUGGGAAGGCAUUCCGUCAUCGCUCAGACCUUAUUGAACACCAGAGAAUUCACACCGGAGAGAGACCCUUUGAAUGCAAUGAGUGUGGGAAAGCCUUUAUUCGGAGUUCAAAGCUCAUUCAGCAUCAGAGGAUCCAUACUGGGGAGAGGCCUUACGUAUGCAAUGAGUGUGGGAAGCGCUUCAGCCAGACGUCAAACUUCACCCAGCAUCAGAGAAUUCACACUGGAGAGAAACUCUAUGAAUGUAACGAGUGUGGGAAAGCUUUCUUUCUGAGUUCAUACCUUAUUCGACACCAGAAAAUCCACACUGGAGAGAGAGUGUAUGAAUGUAAGGAAUGUGGGAAAGCGUUUCUCCAGAAAGCCCAUCUCACUGAGCACCAGAAGAUCCACUCUGGGGACAGGCCCUUCGAAUGUAAAGACUGUGGGAAAGCCUUCAUCCAGAGCUCCAAGCUGCUUCUGCACCAGAUUAUUCACACUGGAGAAAAGCCCUAUGUGUGCAGUUAUUGUGGGAAAGGCUUUAUUCAGAGGUCAAACUUCCUUCAACACCAGAAAAUUCAUACUGAAGAGAAGCUCUAUGAAUGUAGUCAGUAUGGGAGAGAUUUUAACUCAACUACAAACGUUAAAAAUAAUCAAAGGGUUCACCAAGAGGGACUCUCCUUGAGUAAGGCCCCCAUACAUUUGGGUGAGAGGUCUGUAGAUAAGGGGGAACACACAGGUAACUUAUAAAAUAAUUACUUUCCCGCCCAGUGAGUGAUGUUUGGAAAUGCGUGGAAUUAGGAUUCAUGUGGUUUCUAAGAUUUGGACAUGUCAGAAUUUUGUGAGUCAUGGAUGGGGCUGCUUUUGCAGUGGGUGCCACCUGCCACUGUGCAGCCCUACUCGGCUCAGCCCUUCUCCUCAGCUGUGAGCACUGUCCUCAGGAGAGUCACAGGGCUUGACACCUGACUCUGAGCUGGAACAGUAGGGGCAGGGAGAAGACAGGUCUCAAGAAAAGGUUUUUAAGAAGUUUCAUCCCCAGUUAAGCAGAGUCCAUCCUUGACUUAAAUCCCUUAUUACAGCACAACUGUGUAUCUAAUCUUACGAUUUAGGAGAAUGUUACCUAGGACAUUUUGAUGUGUUAAGUUGAAGAAAGGUAACUCGUGUAUGAACCCCGAGCCAUUUCCCUGUUGUCCUGAGGAGGAACUCCAGGCCUCCCAUCGUGUGCCCUAAGGCCUCCUGCGUCCUGGAGCCCUGCCUCCCACUGCCUGACUUCCUGCCACACGGUUAAUGCUGCAGCAACACCGACUGCUUCAUCUUCCCUGUGCUCCACGUGGCUUCCUACCUCUCUCGCCUUUGUUCUUGUUGAAGGGUCUCUUCUCAGCUAAUUAACUCUGAAUCAUGGUUCAAGACAAGCCUCAGGCAUCAUGUCAAUGGGUGUUUCCCUCAAGCUUAGUUGGCAGCACUCUCCACACUUCUGUGGCUCAGUGAUUACUGCUAUUACUAUAUUUACUUGCAUAUGUCAGAAUGAUGUGAUAGACUAUCUCUGUCACUAUGCUGUUGGGUUCCUGAGGACAGUGAUCAUAUCUGAUUGAUUUCCAUGUGUCCACUGUCUAGCACAGGGCAAUAAAAAAUACACCCCUAAAUCUAUGUGUAAUUGGCAUCUCUCUUGCUUUGUCCUUUCUAUACUGCCAUUCUAAAAAUUUUCAGCUGUUGGCUGUUUUUUUUGUUGUUUGUUCAUUUUGUAUCAGUAUAAUCUACGAUUCUGUUAGAAGUAUCUUCUCAGCCCUGCUACUGUCUGCUGCUCCUACUUAGAAGUUGCAGGCAAUAUCCUGUGCACAUCCACGCCCUCCUGUGUGCCACCUUACAGCUCAUGCAGAACUGUCUACUUGAUCUGGAGGGCAUUGACACCUGGCUCAGCUGGAACAGUGGGGACAGGAGGAGGCAGGUCUCAAGAGAAGGUCUUUACUUACUUGUCUGUAUCUUUCUGUCUCACUCGAAAGGCACAGUCUCAAUGCGCUACGUAACUCUUCUGUUGUAGCAGUUCUGAGGUUGAACUGAGCUCUUGUCAUUUUCCAUGCUCUCUGGCUCAUUGUGUCAUUUCAAAAUGUAUUGAUAUCUAUAAGGAAUAGUCCUCAAUGUUGGGAAAACAGAUGAGCAACCCACUACCCUGAAGUCAUCCACCGUGUAGUGGGGAAGACGGAGAUCACAGUAGGGUGAGUUAAGUAUGUGCCCUCAGGUGUGAAGGAGCACAGGUGAGGGGGUGCCUGCUGUGGCACAGAGCUGGGAAGGCCUUACAGAAGAGGUGACAUUUCAGCUGGGCCAGAGAUCAGUAGAGAGCAGCUGAAGAAGAAAAUAGGGUCCAGGAGAGGAAUCUGCAGAAACAUGGAGCCAUGACAGAUGGCUUUUUGGCUAGGACUGUUCGAAAGCAGGCGAGGUAAAUGGACAGUGGACAGCCGCCUCGCCAAACUGUUAGUCUUUACCUCUGAAUUUCAUCUGGACAUGAACCCCAAAGUCCAGUUUUGUAACGAUAUAAUUUUUUUCUCAUGAGGCCAUAUUUUGAGUUCUUAAAUACUACCAACCCUGAACGUCUCAGGACAAAUAAUUCAAAAAAGAGAUCUACAUUUUCUGGAAAAUCAGCAUUACUAGAGAUGUUUCAAAUGUAGAUUUUACCAGACCAUUUUAAUCAACUUUAUUGAGAUUCAAUUUUCAUAUAGUAAAACGCCUAUUUAAGUGUACAAGGUUUUGAAAAAUCUAUACACCUGUGUAACCACCACCACCUGUGUAACCACCACCGCCAGAACCAAAAACGUUUCUGUCACCCAAAGAAGUUCCCUUUUGCCUUUUCCUAGUUAAGCCCACUCCAGCCCCAGAUAACCACUUUCUAUCCUCAUAGAUUAGUGUUGCUUGGUUUAGAGCCUCAUACAAAUGGAUUCAUUUACUAUGUGUUCUUUUGCGUCUGAUGUCUCACUUUGGCAUGUUUUUAGACUCAUCCAAGCU